AGUCAUUUCCUCUUGGAGCCCUACCUCUUCUUCCUCUGUCCCUUACUCCCUGACACACCCGGAGUCCCAACAUUGCCUCCUUUCCUGGCUCUUUCAGGGUGCCCAGGGUGGAGGGGAAGGGGAGUCAGCCAGACCCCCAUCCUGACAAGGCUUGUGGAACUGCUGACUCAGGAUGUCGGGGUUCAGGCUGGGUGACCACGUGUGGCUGGAGCCUCCCUCCACCCACAAGACCGGCGUGGCCAUCGGGGGCAUCAUCAAAGAGGCAAAGCCAGGCAAAGUCUUGGUUGAAGAUGACGAGGGCAAGGAACACUGGAUCCGAGCAGAGGACUUUGGUGUCCUCAGUCCCAUGCACCCCAACUCAGUCCAGGGUGUGGACGACAUGAUCCGCCUGGGGGACCUGAACGAGGCAGGCAUGGUGCACAACCUCCUGAUCCGCUACCAGCAGCACAAGAUCUAUACAUACACAGGCUCCAUCCUGGUGGCCGUCAACCCGUUCCAGGUGCUGCCGCUCUACACCCUGGAGCAGGUACAGCUCUACUACAGCCGCCAUAUGGGCGAGCUGCCCCCGCAUGUCUUUGCCAUCGCCAACAACUGCUACUUCAGCAUGAAGAGGAACAAGAGGGACCAGUGCUGCAUCAUCAGCGGCGAGUCUGGGGCUGGCAAGACGGAGACCACCAAGCUCAUCCUGCAGUUCCUGGCCACCAUCAGUGGCCAGCAUUCGUGGAUUGAGCAGCAGGUCCUGGAAGCCAACCCCAUCCUGGAGGCCUUUGGAAAUGCCAAGACAAUCCGCAACGACAACUCAAGCCGCUUUGGGAAGUACAUUGACAUCUACUUUAACCCCAGCGGGGUGAUCGAGGGCGCGCGCAUCGAGCAAUUUCUCCUGGAGAAGUCCCGGGUCUGCCGGCAGGCUCCCGAGGAGCGGAACUACCAUAUCUUCUACUGCAUGCUCAUGGGGGUGAGUGCUGAGGACAAGCAGCUGCUGAGCCUGGGCACGCCCUCCGAGUACCACUACCUGACCAUGGGGAACUGCACUUCCUGUGAGGGGCUCAACGACGCCAAGGACUACGCCCACAUCCGCUCGGCCAUGAAGAUCCUCCAGUUCUCCGACUCCGAGAGCUGGGACGUCAUCAAGCUGCUGGCUGCCAUUCUCCACCUGGGGAAUGUGGGGUUCAUGGCUUCGGUCUUCGAGAACCUGGACGCCUCAGACGUGAUGGAGACGCCCGCCUUUCCCACCGUGAUGAAGUUACUGGAGGUGCAGCACCAGGAGCUCCGGGACUGUCUGAUCAAGCACACCAUCCUCAUCCGAGGGGAAUUUGUCACCAGGUCCCUGAACAUUGCCCAGGCUGCUGACCGGAGGGACGCCUUUGUCAAGGGCAUCUAUGGGCACCUCUUCCUGUGGAUUGUCAAGAAGAUCAAUGCCGCCAUCUUCACACCACCAGCCCAGGACCCCAAAAAUGUGCGGAGGGCCAUCGGCCUCCUGGACAUAUUUGGCUUUGAAAAUUUCGAGAACAAUAGCUUCGAGCAGCUCUGCAUCAACUUCGCCAACGAGCACCUGCAGCAGUUCUUUGUGCAGCACGUGUUCACCAUGGAGCAAGAGGAGUACCGCUCGGAGAACAUCUCCUGGGACUAUAUCCACUACACCGACAAUCGGCCCACCCUGGACCUGCUGGCCCUCAAGCCCAUGAGCAUCAUCUCCCUCCUGGACGAAGAAAGCCGCUUCCCGCAGGGGACAGAUCUCACCAUGCUGCAAAAGCUGAACAGCGUCCAUGCCAACAACAAGGCCUUCCUACAGCCCAAGAACAUCCACGAUGCCAGAUUUGGCAUUGCCCAUUUUGCCGGCGAGGUGUACUACCAAGCAGAAGGCUUCCUGGAGAAGAACCGAGACGUGCUGAGCACAGAUAUCCUCACCCUGGUUUACUCCUCCAAAAACAAGUUUCUGAGGGAGAUAUUCAACUUGGAGUUAGCAGAGACCAAGCUGGGCCAUGGGACCAUCCGCCAGGCAAAGGCAGGAAACCAUCUCUUCAAGUCUGCAGACUCAAAUAAACGGCCCUCCACCUUAGGAAGCCAGUUCAAACAGUCUCUGGACCAGCUGAUGAAAAUCCUGACCAACUGCCAGCCUUACUUCAUCCGCUGCAUCAAACCUAAUGAGUACAAGAAGCCGCUGCUGUUCGACCGGGAGCUGUGCCUGCGGCAGCUGCGAUACUCGGGCAUGAUGGAGACCGUGCACAUCCGCAAGUCGGGCUUCCCCAUCCGCUACACGUUCGAGGAGUUCUCGCAGAGGUUCGGCGUGUUGCUGCCCAACGCCAUGCGGAUGCAGCUGCAAGGCAAGCUCCGCCAGAUGACCCUGGGCAUCACUGACGUGUGGCUGCGGACAGACAAAGACUGGAAAGCGGGGAAGACAAAAAUUUUCCUGAGGGAUCAUCAGGACACUCUGCUGGAGGUACAGAGAAGCCAGGUGCUAGACAGAGCGGCGCUCAGCAUCCAGAAAGUCCUUCGGGGCUACAGAUACAGGAAGGAGUUCCUGAGGCAGAGGCGGGCAGCUGUGACCCUGCAGGCCUGGUGGAGAGGCUACUGCAACAGGAGGAAUUUCAAGCUGAUCCUCGUGGGCUUUGAGCGCCUGCAGGCUAUUGCCCGGAGCCAGCCGCUGGCGAGGCAGUACCAGGCCAUGCGGCAGAGGACAGUCCAGCUGCAGGCCCUGUGCAGGGGAUACCUGGUGCGCCAGCAAGUCCAGGCCAAGAGGAGGGCAGUGGUGGUCAUUCAGGCCCAUGCCAGGGGCAUGGCUGCCCGGCGCAACUUCCAGCAAAGGAAGGCCAAUGGUAUGCAGGCGCCGCUGGUCAUCCCGGCCGAGGGGCAGAAAAGCCAAGGCGCUCUCCCUGCCAAGAAGCGCAGAUCCAUCUACGACACCGUCACUGACACGGAGAUGGUGGAGAAGGUGUUCGGCUUCCUCCCUGCCAUGAUUGGGGGCCAGGAGGGCCAGGCCUCGCCGCACUUUGAGGAUCUGGAAUCGAAGACCCAGAAGCUGCUUGAGGUUGACCUGGACACAGUCCCCAUGGCGGAGGAGCCUGAGGAGGAUGUGGAUGGCCUGGCCGAGUACACCUUCCCCAAGUUUGCUGUGACUUACUUCCAGAAAUCAGCCAGCCACACACACAUCCGGCGGCCCCUCCGAUACCCGUUGCUUUACCACGAAGAUGACACUGACUGCUUGGCCGCCCUGGUCAUAUGGAACGUCAUCCUGAGGUUCAUGGGUGAUCUCCCAGAGCCAGUGCUGUAUGCCAGGAGCAGCCAGCAGGGCAGCUCAGUGAUGCGGCAGAUCCAUGACACGCUGGGCAGGGAGCACGGUGCCCAGGUUCCACAGCACAGUAGAUCUGCACAGAGAUCUGGCUGCAAGGACAAGGGGACCAAGGAUAUCUCCUCCAUGAAGCUGAAGCGGUCCUCCCGGAUCACAGGCCAGGUGGCCAGCCAGCUGAACAUUGGAGAGGAGGCAUUGGAGCCUGAUGGCCUUGGUGCAGACCGGCCCAUGUCCAACCUGGAGAAGGUGCACUUCAUCGUGGGCUACGCCAUCCUGCGGCCCAGCCUCAGGGAUGAGAUUUACUGCCAGAUCUGCAAGCAGCUCUCGGAGAACUUCAAAACAAGCAGCCUGGCCCGGGGCUGGAUCCUGCUCAGCCUCUGCCUCGGCUGCUUCCCACCCUCAGAGAGGUUCAUGAAGUAUCUACUGAACUUCAUCGGCCAAGGGCCGGCGACCUACGGCCCCUUCUGUGCCGAGCGCCUGAGACGCACCUAUGCCAAUGGGGUGCGUGCGGAGCCCCCCACCUGGCUGGAGCUGCAGGCUGUCAAGUCCAAGAAGCACAUCCCCAUCCAAGUCAUCUUGGCCACUGGAGAGAGCCUAACCGUCCCCGUGGACUCAGCCUCCACAUCUCGGGAAAUGUGCAUGCACAUCGCUCACAAGCAGGGCCUCAGCGACCACCUGGGCUUCUCCCUCCAGGUCGCCGUGUACGACAAGUUCUGGUCCCUGGGCAGCGGGCGCGACCACAUGAUGGAUGCCAUCGCCCGGUGUGAGCAGAUGGCCCAGGAGAGGGGCGAGAGCCAGCGCCAGUCACCCUGGCGCAUCUACUUCCGGAAGGAAUUCUUCACCCCCUGGCACGACUCCCGGGAGGACCCUGUCAGCACCGAGCUUAUUUACCGCCAAGUCCUCCGAGGAGUCUGGUCUGGCGAGUACAGCUUCGAGAAGGAGGAAGAGCUGGUUGAGCUGCUGGCCCGGCACUGCUACGUGCAGCUCGGCGCCUCAGCAGAGAGCAAGGCUGUCCAGGAGCUGCUGCCCAGCUGCAUCCCCCACAAGCUGUACAGGACCAAGCCCCCAGACAGGCCCCAUACACUCAGAAGCAAGUCACACCACUGGCCGUGCGAGAGCAGGUGGUGGACGCCGCCCGCCUGCAGUGGCCGCUGCUCUUCUCCCGGCUCUUCGAAGUCAUCACACUCUCAGGUAAUGGCAUCUGACAGGGGGCAGGGAGCAGGUAUGGGCUGGGCACCCAGGGGUCCCAUGCAGCCUUCACACUGCCGUCUCUCCUGGCCAGGCCCCCGCCUGCCCAAGACGCAGCUGAUCUUGGCUGUUAACUGGAAGGGGCUUUGCUUCCUGGACCAGCAGGAGAAGAUGCUGCUGGAACUCUCUUUCCCAGAGGUCAUGGGUCUGGCCACCAACAGGGAGGCCCAGGGCGGGCAGAGGCUGCUGCUCUCCACGAUGCAUGAGGAGUACGAGUUUGUGUCACCCAGCAGUGUGGCCAUCGCUGAGCUGGUGGCCCUGUUCCUGGAGGGCCUGAAGGAGAGGUCCAUUUUCGCCAUGGCCCUGCAGGACAGGAAGGCCACAGAUGACACCACCCUCCUGGCCUUCAAGAAGGGGGACCUGUUGGUCCUCACAAAGAAGCAGGGGCUGCUGGCCUCUGAGAACUGGACCCUCGGCCAGAACGACAGGACAGGCAAGACGGGGCUGGUGCCCAUGGCCUGCCUCUACACCAUCCCCACGGUCACUAAGCCCUCGGCACAGCUGCUGAGCUUGCUUGCCAUGUCACCAGAGAAGAGGAAGCUGGCGGCUCAGGAGGGGCAGUUCACAGAGCCACGUCCUGAGGAGCCACCCAAGGAAAAGCUGCACACCCUGGAGGAGUUCUCCUAUGAGUUCUUCAGGGCUCCAGAGAAGGACAUGGUGAGCAUGGCCGUGCUGCCCCUGGCCCGUGCCCGUGGCCACCUGUGGGCCUAUUCCUGCGAGCCGCUGCGACAGCCGCUGCUCAAGCGAGUCCACGCCAACGUCGACCUCUGGGACAUCGCCUGCCAGAUCUUUGUCGCCAUCCUCCGGUACAUGGGCGACUACCCUUCUCGGCAGGCCUGGCCCACCCUGGAGCUCACCGACCAGAUCUUCACACUGGCCCUGCAGCACCCGGCCCUCCAGGACGAGGUCUACUGCCAGAUCCUGAAGCAGCUGACGCACAACUCCAACAGGCACAGCGAAGAGCGGGGCUGGCAGCUGCUGUGGCUGUGCACGGGCCUCUUCCCGCCCAGCAAGGGGCUGCUGCCCCAUGCCCAGAAGUUUAUAGACACUCGGAGGGGGAAGCUGCUGGCCCCCGACUGCAGCCGCCGAAUCCAGAAGGUCCUGAGGACGGGGCCCCGGAAGCAGCCCCCGCACCAGGUGGAGGUGGAGGCCGCAGAGCAGAACGUCUCCCGCAUCUGCCACAAGAUCUACUUCCCCAAUGACACCAGUGAGAUGCUGGAGGUGGUUGCCAACACACGGGUGCGGGAUGUGUGUGACAGCAUUGCCACCAGGCUGCAGCUGGCCUCCUGGGAGGGCUGCAGCCUCUUCAUCAAGAUUUCAGACAAGGUCAUCAGCCAGAAGGAGGGAGACUUCUUCUUUGAUUCCUUGAGGGAGGUGUCUGACUGGGUGAAGAAGAACAAGCCCCAGAAAGAAGGGGCCCCCGUGACGCUCCCCUACCAGGUGUACUUCAUGCGGAAAUUGUGGCUCAACAUAUCUCCAGGGAAGGAUGUGAAUGCAGACACCAUACUCCAUUACCACCAGGAGCUGCCCAAGUACCUGCGCGGAUUCCACAAGUGUUCGCGGGAGGAUGCCAUCCACCUGGCGGGCCUCAUCUACAAGGCCCAGUUCAACAACGACCGGUCCCAGCUGGCUAGUGUCCCCAAGAUCCUGAGGGAACUGGUGCCUGAGAACCUCACACGCCUGAUGUCCUCGGAGGAGUGGAAAAAGAGCAUCCUUCUAGCCUAUGACAAGCAUAAGGACAAGACAGUGGAGGAGGCCAAGGUGGCCUUCCUGAAGUGGAUCUGCCGGUGGCCCACCUUCGGAUCCGCCUUCUUCGAGGUGAAGCAAACCUCGGAGCCUUCCUACCCGGACGUCAUCCUCAUCGCCAUCAACCGACAUGGGGUUCUGCUCAUCCACCCCAAGACCAAGGACCUGCUCACCACCUAUCCCUUCACCAAGAUCUCCAGCUGGAGCAGCGGCAGCACCUACUUCCACAUGGCGCUGGGGAGCCUGGGCCGUGGCAGCCGCCUGCUGUGCGAGACCUCCCUGGUGAGCUCAGGUUCUUUCUCCCAUCCAAGAUGCAUAGGACAGAGCUGCUGGAGACUGGGUUCCCCACCCUCACCCCUUUCAAGUGGCUCACUAAGAGGGCUCAGUCACAGGGCCCAGGCGGGGCCAGCAGAUCUGGAGAGGGCCUGGGUGCAUCCCCAGGACCAGCAGCCAAGGUGGCAAGGCCAGGCGGGACCCCCUGCGCCCUUGGCCCAUUCCAAGGAGGGAGGGAGACCCAGCUCCAGCAGGGCAAGCAGAAAUGACGGCCCCAAUGGCAGGAGCCCGCCUUCCCUUUCUCCAUGCCCUGCACUGCUGGUUGCUGAGGAAGAGAAGGUGGUCCCUGAGUCCAGGACCCCCACCUGCCCUCUGCACCCACAGCCUCUGACCCCCCCGUCCCCUGUCCAGGGCUAUAAGAUGGAUGACCUGCUGACCUCAUAUGUGCAGCAGCUCCUGAGUGCCAUGAACAAGCAGCGGGGCUCCAAGGCCCCAGCCCUGGCCAGCACCUAGCAGCGGAUGCUGGCGUGUCUGCUCAGGCGCCCUUCCCGACCUCUAGCCUGGCGGCACCUUCCCAGGCCCUCUCAACCCAGGGCCUGUCCUUGGCGGGCAGCCUUCCAUGCUGCCCCCCAUACAAAGCCCACUCAGCCCCGCAGGCGGCCCCCUCUGUCCUGGGCGCUGCCCAGGGAGGCCAAAAGACGGGCCCAGAAUGGGGUCGGGAGUCUCGGACCCCCAGGCUAUUGGUGGAUGACUGACUGACAGGACACCUCCCAACCCCACCCCACCCCACCAGAAUGUUCAAUAAAAACUCCUGGAGCAGGA